ACUUGGCCCGCGCUUAGGGCCCUCGCGGGGGGCUUGUGGGUCCUCCUCCCCCUCCCACUGACAACUGCCCCAACUGCUCUUCCCGCCCCGGUCACAGUGAAAAUGUAGACGGGGUCGUUGUCCACUAUGUUAGGUCUUAAUGGUGGGAGGACGCCCGAGUGCUCGGCCCGUUUCACCCCGAGGAGGAAGGACACUGGGUCAUGACGCCAUCAGAGGGCGCCAGAGCAGGGACCGGACGCGAGUUGGAGAUGUUGGACUCGCUGUUGGCCUUGGGCGGCCUGGUGCUGCUUCGGGAUUCCGUGGAGUGGGAGGGGCGCAGUCUCUUGAAGGCGCUUGUCAAGAAAUCUGCACUGUGUGGGGAGCAAGUGCAUAUCCUGGGCUGUGAAGUGAGCGAGGAAGAGUUUCGUGAAGGUUUUGACUCUGAUAUCAACAAUCGGCUGGUUUACCAUGACUUCUUCAGAGACCCUCUCAACUGGUCAAAAACUGAGGAGGCCUUUCCUGGGGGGCCGCUGGGAGCCUUGAGAGCCAUGUGCAAGAGGACAGAUCCUGUUCCUGUCACCAUUGCUCUCGAUUCACUCAGCUGGCUGCUACUUCGCCUUCCCUGCACCACACUCUGCCAGGUCCUGCAUGCUGUGAGCCAUCAGGACUCUUGUCCUGGUGACAGCUCCUCAGUGGGGAAAGUGAGUGUGCUGGGCUUGCUACAUGAAGAGCUUCAUGGACCAGGCCCUGUGGGAGCUCUCAGCAGCCUUGCUCAGACUGAGGUGACCCUGGGCGGUACCAUGGGCCAGGCCUCGGCCCACAUCCUGUGUCGGAGGCCCCGACAGCGCCCAACUGACCAGACUCAGUGGUUCUCCAUCCUUCCGGACUUCAGCCUGGAUCUCCAAGAGGGGCCCUCUGUAGAGUCCCAGCCCUACUCCGAUCCUCAUAUACCCCCGGUAUCUAAGAAUGCCAAGGCCAGAACAAGGAAAUGUAGUUUAGUAUCUGGUCACGGGAGAGAAAAUAAAAGCUGCAGAGGUUGGGGGUGGGGUCAGGGAUUCUAGGGAUGGGGCAGAGUGGCAGCAUCCUUUGUACCUACAGGUGGAUCCCACAACUCAUUUGACCUUUAACCUUCACCUGUCCAAGAAAGAGAGAGAAGCCAGAGAUAGCCUGAUCCUGCCCUUCCAGUUCAGUUCUGAAAAGUAAGGUUGGGACCUGGGUACGUGGAUCCCUGAGUAGAUCCCAGCAUCUGGGCCAUGGAGAGGUUGGGGCAACAGGUUAUUGAUUAACCUGACUUUAUAGGGACUGAAGUCCACCUCCAGAGACAAGUCCAAGUUCUUGAUCCACCCAUUCCCCCUAUAAUGGCAGAGGACCUUUAUGUCUCUUUUCUCUCCCUUAUACCCUUGGGUCACAGCUCCAGUUGUCCCCAGAGCACCCUGGGCCUGGGCUGAGCCAGACCAGACCCUUGGGAGGUGGCCCUAUCCCUAGGCAGUGGUGCUAGGAGGACAGAAGGCUAUAUGGGCGUGGCAGAGGCUGGUUAACAAGGGCUUAGUACACGCUUGCUGUUCUGUGCCCAGUAUGUGGGCGGAUGACGCAAGACUACAAGAUCCUUGCCCUCAAGCUGCUAGGAACUUACGGUUUUAUUAGGAGAGCAGUACAAGGGUAUCUAUCCCAGUACCAAAUGGUGCUUCAGCUCUAACAUGGAGGUCAGAGAAAGGGACUUGGACCAAUAAAAUGACAUGGAGGCCUAACAGGUUGCCUGAAUGAGAGUCACAGUCACCUGGAAGAAAGUAUCCAGACCCAACCUGUUAGCUACCCUCACCAGCACCAAAUCUUCCCUUCUCAGACAGCAGGCUCUCCUGCGGCCUAGGCCAGGGCAGGCUACCAGCCACAUCUUCUAUGAGCCAGAUGCUUAUGAUGACCUGGACCAAGAAGACCCAGAUGACGACCUGGAUAUUUGACUGGCCAGAUUUGAUUAGAUUGUAAUUGGAGGGGGCGCGGGAAGACUUUGGGCCCAGAACCAUCUUUCUAUUGUUUGUGUUAGCCUUACCCUGUCCCUGCCCCACCUUGGUUCCCCUUGUCUAUGGAGCCCCGCCUUGUGAGCCAGGAAGCAGCGUCUCAUCAGGACAGAAGGUAGGAUGAAGACAUGGGGUAAUGUGAGAGAGUAGAACACCCCCGUACCUAAUAAAAAUCUUUAUUUUUUUAUUAAAAAA